GUUGGCUCUCGCUGCACGCGGAGGUCAAGGUGUCGUCCUUACUGCUGUGUGUCGUCCGCUCCUAAAGGCCCAGCUUCUAUGGCCCUGUGACCUGCAGGUAUUGGGAGAUUCACAACUAAGUCGCCAGGACCCCCGGAAGCCUAGAAAUGGGAUCGUUGACAUUUCGGGAUGUGGCCAUACAAUUCUCUCUGGAGGAGUGGCAAUGCCUGGACACUGCACAGCAGAAUUUAUAUAGGAAUGUGAUGUUAGAGAACUACAGAAACCUGGUCUUCCUGGGUAUUGCUGCCCCUAAGCCAGACCUGAUCAUUUUUCUGGAGCAAGGAAAAGAGCCCUGGAAUAUGAAGAGACAUGAGCUGGUGAAAGAACCGCCAGUUAUAUGUUCUCAUUUUGCUCAAGACCUUUGGCCAGAGCAGGGCAGAGAAGAUUCUUUCCAAAAAGUGAUAUUGAGAAGAUAUGAAAAAUGUGGACAUGAGAAUUUACAGUUAAAAAUUGGUUGUACCAAUGUGGAUGAGUGUAAGGUGCACAAAAAAGGUUAUAAUAAGCUUAACCAGAGUUUGACAACUACACAAAGCAAAGUAUUUCAAUGUGGCAAAUAUGCAAACAUCUUUCAUAAAUGUUCAAAUUCAAAAAGACAUAAGAUAAGGCAUACUGGAAAGAAACUUUUGAAAUGUAAAGAAUAUGUCAGAUCAUUUUGCAUGCUUUCACACCUAUCUCAACAUAAAAGAAUUUAUACUAGAGAGAAUUCCUACAAAAGUGAAGAACAUGGCAAAGCCUUUAACUGGUCCUCAGCCCUUACUUAUAAGAGAAUUCAUACUGGAGAGAAACCCUGCAAAUGUGAAGAAUGUGGCAAAGCCUUUAGUAAGUUCUCAAUCCUUACUAAGCAUAAGGUAAUUCAUACUGGAGAGAAACAUUACAAAUGUGAAGAAUGUGGCAAAGCCUUCACCCGGUCCUCAAGCCUUAUUGAACAUAAGAGAAGUCAUGCUGGAGAGAAACCCUACAAAUGUGAAGAAUGUGGCAAAGCCUUUAGUAAGGCCUCAACCCUUACUGCACAUAAGACAAUUCAUGCUGGAGAGAAACCCUACAAAUGUGAAGAAUGUGGCAAAGCUUUCAACCGGUCCUCAAACCUUAUGGAACAUAAGAGAAUUCAUACUGGAGAGAAGCCCUGCAAAUGUGAAGAAUGUGGCAAAGCCUUUGGUAACUUCUCAACCCUUACUAAACAUAAGGUAAUUCAUACUGGAGAGAAACCCUACAAAUGUGAAGAAUGUGGCAAAGCCUUCAGCUGGCCCUCAAGCCUUACUGAACACAAGAGAAUUCAUGCUGGAGACAAACCUUACAAAUGUGAAGAAUGUGGCAAAACCUUUAAGUGGUCCUCAACACUUACUAAACAUAAGAUAAUUCAUACUGGAGAGAAACCCUACAAAUGUGAAGAAUGUGGCAAAGCCUUUACUACAUUUUCGAGCCUUACUAAACAUAAAGUAAUUCAUACUGGAGAGAAACACUACAAAUGUGAAGAAUGUGGCAAAGUCUUCAGCUGGUCCUCAAGCCUUACUACACAUAAGGCAAUUCAUGCUGGAGAGAAACUCUACAAAUGUGAAGAAUGUGGCAAAGCCUUUAAGUGGUCCUCAAACCUUAUGGAACAUAAGAGAAUUCAUACUGGAGAGAAACCCUACAAAUGUGAAGAAUGUGGCAAAGCCUUCAGUAAGGUUGCAAACCUUACUAAACAUAAGGUAAUUCAUACUGGAGAGAAACAAUACAAAUGUGAAGAAUGUGGCAAAGCCUUCAUCUGGUCCUCAAGACUUAGUGAACAUAAGAGAAUUCAUACUGGAGAGAAACCCUACAAAUGUGAAGAAUGUGGCAAAGCCUUUAGCUGGGUCUCAGUCCUUAACAAACAUAAGAAAAUUCAUGCUGGAAAGAAAUUCUACAAAUGUGAAGAAUGUGGUAAAGACUUCAACCAAUCCUCACACCUUACUACUCAUAAGAGAAUUCAUACUGGAGGAAAAACCCUACAAAUGUGAAAAAUGUGGCAAAGCUUUCAAUUAGUUCUUAACCCUUACUGAACAUAAGGGUAUUUAUACAGGAGGGAAACCCUACAAAUGUGAAGAAUGUGGCAAAUUUUUUAACUGUUCCUCAAUCCUUACUAAACAUAAGGUAAUUCAUACUGGAGGGAAUUCCUACAAUUGUGUGGAAUGUGGCAAAGCCUUUAAUCAGUCCUUAAGGCUUACUACGUACAAGACAACUCAUACUGGAGAGAAACCAUACACGUGUGAAGAAUGUGGGAAAGCCUCUAACAGAUCCUCAAUUCUUAACAGACAUAAGCUAAUUCAUACUAGAGAGAAACUGCAAACCUGAAAGAUGUGACAAGGCUUUUGGCAACACCUGAAACUUUUCUGAAUAUAAAAGAAAUCAUACUGGUGAGAAAUCCUAGAAAUGUGAAGAAUGUGACAAAGCCUUUAAAUGGCUGUCACACUUGAUUGUAGGUAAGAUAUCUCAUACUGGAGAAAACUACUAGAAUAAACAAUGUGGCAAAACAUUUAACCAAUGCUCAUGCCUAAUUGCAAAGGAAAGCAUUUACACUAGCCUGGGCAACAGAGGGAGACUGU